AAAUAUACGUCUGUCACAGUUAACGGCAAAGCCUAGGGCAAGAGUUCUACGCCCAAGAUGGCCAGCCGGAAGCGGGCUUCUCGCGACCAUGUGGCGAAGCCCCAUUCGUCAGCUGGCCGCCCGCGGCCCUGGUACCCGGUCACCUCUCUGAUCUGCGCAUGUGCUGGGCUACGCCCGGGCGCAAGCGCCAAGAGCGGCUGCGUCUAUGGUCAUGACGUCUGACAGAGCGUCCACCCGUCUUCGACAGGACUCUAUGGUUCUUACGCGCGCAGACAGACCGCCUAUAUAAGCCAUGCGCAGGCGGAGGAGCGCCUCUUUCCCUUCGGUGUGGUGACCACUGAAGAUCCUGGUGUCGCCAUGGGCCGCCGCCCCGCCCGUUGUUACCGGUAUUGUAAGAACAAGCCGUACCCAAAGUCUCGCUUCUGCCGAGGUGUCCCUGAUGCCAAGAUUCGCAUUUUUGACCUGGGGCGGAAAAAGGCAAAAGUGGAUGAGUUUCCGCUUUGUGGCCACAUGGUGUCAGAUGAAUAUGAGCAGCUGUCCUCUGAAGCCCUGGAGGCUGCCCGAAUUUGUGCCAAUAAGUACAUGGUAAAAAGUUGUGGCAAAGAUGGCUUCCAUAUCCGGGUGCGGCUCCACCCCUUCCACGUCAUCCGCAUCAACAAGAUGUUGUCCUGUGCUGGGGCUGACAGGCUCCAAACAGGCAUGCGAGGUGCCUUUGGAAAGCCCCAGGGCACUGUGGCCAGGGUUCACAUUGGCCAAGUUAUCAUGUCCAUCCGCACCAAGCUGCAGAACAAGGAGCAUGUGAUUGAGGCCCUGCGCAGGGCCAAGUUCAAGUUUCCUGGCCGCCAGAAGAUCCACAUCUCAAAGAAGUGGGGCUUCACCAAGUUCAAUGCUGAUGAAUUUGAAGACAUGGUGGCUGAAAAGCGGCUCAUCCCAGAUGGCUGUGGGGUCAAGUACAUCCCCAGUCGUGGCCCUCUGGACAAGUGGCGGGCCCUGCACUCAUGAGGGCUUCCAAUGUGCUGCCCCCCUCUUAAUACUCACCAAUAAAUUCUACUUCCUGUCCACCUAUGUCUUUGUAUCUACAUUCUUGACGGGGAAGGAACUUCCUCUGGGAACCUUUGGGUCAUUGCCCUUUCACUUCAGAAACAGGUUGACAACUCAGCCCUGCUCAUGAGGCAGCAAACCCUGCAAAGGGCUGGGACUGGUGGCCUUAUGUCAGUUGUCUACUCUGGAGCUUGACUUGGACCUCCCCAGGUCCUAGGCAGUAGGUUGAAAAACACUGAAGUGCUUUUCAUGAAGCACAGCUGCAGCAAAGCCUUGCAAUCCCAGGCUGGGGUCAGCCUACAGUUGUGUUGCUUAUUACAACACAUGCGGACCAAGAGGGGCUUGUGGGCUAGAGGCUGACCAGCAGCGUUUAUUUAGCAAGGGUAGGUGUGCAUCACAUUGGGCUUGUUCUCACCCAUCUGGUUUGGCCAUUCCUCCUUGGUGGGAAUCAUCCAGGUACUGCUGAGGUCACCUGCGAUUUGCCCCAUUUCCUAUCUCUAGCAACCUCCUGGGCCCCAUGCCCCCACCCCUUCUAGAACCUGCAUUCCCAGGGCCUUCACCACCUGACCAAAGGUCUAGGCUAACCUUUGGUCAUUUGUAACAAGACCUCGGAACAGACACGUGUGUGGCAUGGUUUGGCCUGGGGAUCUUAGAUGUCUGACCUGAACUAUUGUAGAACAGCGCUGGCUUUUGGGGGAGCAGCAAAAAUGAGAGGAGUGCUAGGUGGGUGGCCUGAGCAUCUGUAUCCAGGGACAGGACUCCAAAGGCUUUUGGUCCCAGAGCUGGGGUAUGUUGGCCCCAGCCCCCAGCCUGUGGCUCCCAAAAGGCCUCUGGUUUUUUGUAAUCUCAGUUUACAGCCAUUUCUUAGGUUUUUAAUUACCUUUAUUUUAUUUUGCCAAACAUACCUGGGAAUACCUUUUAUUUUUUUUUUACCUUGGGGUGAUGGUUCCAAACCAUAAAUGUGAUUAUAGUUAACACAUGACCCUUCUAGCGUCCCAGCCAGUGUUUUUCCUGACCUCUCUUCUUUGGAGAGGAGGAUGGAAGGGAGGGGUCCGGCAUGCUGCUGGCAUUUUGCUGUGUCCUGCAGCCCCUUUCCGGGACACCUGGGUUCACACAGCUUUUUAGCUUACAUAACUGGUGCAGAUUUUCUGUGUGGAGAUGUUGCCUUGACCAGCCUUGGCUGGACUUUACCAGGCAUGCAGAAGCCUGUACCAACACAGACUACAGCACCCAGGAGGUGCGAGUGUGGCUGCUCAGCGGUUAUAACAGGCCUGACUGCAUUGUUCACCGGAUUAUAAUGAGCCAAAAUGUUUCCCGGUGUUUGCUGGUUUCAGGGAAGGAGUUUGAUAUAGCAGAUUAACCACCCUCCUUGUAGCUAUUGGGGCUUAAUGGUUUCCUGGUGAUUCUUACCAAUCCACAAUAAACAUGGCCCAUUGGCAUAUCUGC